GCAGUGCUGCCAACGCCCCGGUGGAGAAGCUGAGACGGAGUCUCACUGUGUUGCCCAGGCUGGAGUGCAGUGGCGCCAUCUUGGCUCACUGCAGUGCGCCUCUGCCCCCCGAGUUCAAGCGAUUCUCCUGCCUCAGGCUCCUGAGUAGCUGGGACUACAGGUCAUCAUCAGAUUUGAAAUAUUUAAAGUGGAUACAAAACUAUUUCAGCAAUGCAGACAAUUAAGUGUGUUGUUGUGGGCGAUGGUGCUGUUGGUAAAACAUGUCUCCUGAUAUCCUACACAACAAACAAAUUUCCAUCGGAAUAUGUACCGACUGUUUUUGACAACUAUGCAGUCACAGUUAUGAUUGGUGGAGAACCAUAUACUCUUGGACUUUUUGAUACUGCAGGGCAAGAGGAUUAUGACAGAUUACGACCGCUGAGUUAUCCACAAACAGAUGUAUUUCUAGUCUGUUUUUCAGUGGUCUCUCCAUCUUCAUUUGAAAACGUGAAAGAAAAGUGGGUGCCUGAGAUAACUCACCACUGUCCAAAGACUCCUUUCUUGCUUGUUGGGACUCAAAUUGAUCUCAGAGAUGACCCCUCUACUAUUGAGAAACUUGCCAAGAACAAACAGAAGCCUAUCACUCCAGAGACUGCUGAAAAGCUGGCCCGUGACCUGAAGGCUGUCAAGUAUGUGGAGUGUUCUGCACUUACACAGAAAGGCCUAAAGAAUGUAUUUGACGAAGCAAUAUUGGCUGCCCUGGAGCCUCCAGAACCGAAGAAGAGCCGCAGGUGUGUGCUGCUAUGAACAUCUCUCCAGAGCCCUUUCUGCACAGCUGGUGUCGGCAUCAUACUAAAAGCAAUGUUUAAAUCAAACUAAAGAUUAAAAAUUAAAAUUCGUUUUUGCAAUAAUGACAAAUGCCCUGCACCUACCCACAUGCACUCGUGUGAGACAAGGCCCAUAGGUAUGGCCCCCCCCUUCCCCCUCCCAGUACUAGUUAAUUUUGAGUAAUUGUAUUGUCAGAAAAGUGAUUAGUACUAUUUUUUUUUGUUGUUUCAAAAAAAAAAUUUUUGUGUGUGUGUGUUUUUUUUUUUUUUUUUUUUGUUGUUUAAAAGCAAGGCAUGCUUGUGGAUGACUCUGUAACAGACUAAUUGGAAUUGUUGAAGCUGCUCCCUGGUUCCACUCUGGAGAGUAAUCUGGGACAUCUUAGUGUUUUGUUUUGUUUUUUUCCCUCCUCUUUUUUUUGGGGGGGAGUGUGUGUGGGGUUUGUUUUUUAGUCUUGUUUUUUUAAUUCAUUAACCAGUGGUUAGCCCUUAAGGGGAGGAGGACGGAUUGAUUCCACAUUCCACUUCCUAGAUCUAGUUUAGAAAACAUGUUCCCCAUCUGGUGCUCUUAGGAAGGAGUAUAGUAAAUGCCUCAUUUAAUAACAUACUCCUUUUUGAAAGUUGCCUUUUCUCUCCACCCUUGAGUAGAUCCAGUAUUUGAUGAAACUCAUGAAAGUGGGUGGAGCCCAUCUUGCCCCUCCUCUUUUCUAGGACGCACUAUAUGUGACUGUGACUUUCAAGGACAUUUGUUUGCCAUUUGCUGAUUUUUUUGGGAAGUUAAUUUCUAACUUCUUUCACUGAUAAAUGAAGAAAAGUAUUGCACCUUUGAAAUGCACCAAAUGAAUUGAGUUUGUAAUUAAAAAAAUUUUUUUCCCUUUCAGUCAUUGUCUUAUAUGCUUAGCAUAGAUUUGCAGCUCAGUAGUAUAUGGUGUUCCUAGAAUGCAGCUGAAGACCUGUUAUGUAGAGGAAAUACGAGGGGUGGUGCUAGAAGACAGACAUCUGUGGAAUGAUUCACAUCCUCUCAAGUUAGGAGGAUGGAGGCCUGCUUCAUUAAGAAGCUGGGGGUAGGGUGGGGGUGGGGAGAACACUUAACAACAUGGGGACCAGUCAGGGGAAUCCCCUUAUUUCUGUUUUGCAUAUGAGGAACCCUAGAGCAGCCAGGUGAGGCUCUCUAGUUUAAUAAAAAUCAUGGAAAGACUCUUAAUGCAGACUCUUCUUAAGUGUUAAUAGGGAUUUUUUCAGCUUAUUUUGGUUGCAGUUUCCAAUUUUUAAAAAUGUUGAGGUAAUCUUUCCCACCUUCCCAAACCUAAUUCUUGUAGAUGCAUUAGUGUUGAACCAAUGCUUUCUCAUGUCUCAAUUCUUUGUAUAUGCAUUCUUUUCAGAUGUAUUAAACAAACAAAAACCCUUCACAAGCCAGCCUGAGGGUUGUUAUUUUCCCUCCGUCUCUUACUUUUCAGAUAUUGAGGAGUGGGAAUUUGACUCUUGAUAACAUCAAUUUCUAACAAACUUUGGGAUAAAAUUUUAAAGCUUUAUUAUUUUUAUUUUCUGGCAUUUUAGUUUGAGAUAAUAUUUAGCCCUCUAUAUGUUCAGGUUUGUGCUUUCUCCUCUAAGUUUGACCCUUCCCUUAAAUACCAAGUAGGUCCAUAAUAAUUCUUAGUGAAGCAGUGUUCAGGAAGCUCACUGCUCAUGGUGGAAGGAAAUGUCAGUGUACCUUUAAUCCAUAGAUCAUUGAAAAGCAGCUCAUUUUCCCCCAAGUUUUCUGCAUCAGUGGUUCUCCAACUGGAGUGCAGCUUGAACAAUGUGAUUUUUAAGUUUUCCAGGCAUUUCUAAAAUGUAGCCAAGUUUGGGAAUCACCACACCUAGUUGGUUAUCUCAAACUACUACUAUCAGAAUACAGGUUCUGUGCUGCGAAUCUGAAUAUGGGAUACAUUUUCUUUAGGUAGCAAGAAAGGUUUAUUUACCUUUAGGACAUUAUACUGAUCUGCAUGAGAAUCUUAGAAACUAAGAACCCUUAAAAUCAGUUAAGGUUGGUACACUGUGGCCUCAUUUUGAUAGUUCUCUGCAUGGAGUCAUGUUUGGCAUGAUUUGCAUACUGUGCUAGAAUUAAGCUGGGUUGGUUGAGAAGGGGUUAGGAAGAGGCAGAUGUAAGCUUUAACAGUUCUAACCAAGAAAUGCAUCUUAUUUAUUCCUUGUUGACUAUACUAGGGAGAGAUACCUGGAUCAUGUGAUACCCUGGAAAGCAGGGACAUAUGUAUCCUUAGUGUAGUCAGGGGCGUAUAGGUCCUUGACUAUUGCUAUAUCUUUGUCCUAAAGCAAUGCUUGACAUGAUAUGGCUCUAGAAGUAGUCAUUGGAUGGGUAUAUUAUUUUAUAAAUGAGUAAGUGAAAUAAAGCAGGUCAUACAGUUGUGUCAACGAAUUAUCCGUGUAUCAGAAGAACAAGGAUGAUGGGGAUUGAUUGAAGCUAAUGUUUUCUUAAAUAUUUUCAGAUUGAUUUCUGCAUGUCAGAAGAACUUGGGUAGCAAGUGGAUGCAGCUUAGGUUUUCCAUUUAAAUAUUGUUUUCUAUUUGACGUAACAAACUUGCUUAUAGUCGUGGCUUAGAAGGUGAGUGAUAUUCUCCAGGGAGUAUGAUUUAGAGGCUGGAAAGGGUUAUUGAAAAUAGUCCUUACAGGCUUAGUUUGUGUCAGAAUUUAUAGUAUUUAAUACGAUGUUAAUAUAUUAUUGCUAUUUAUAAGUGUUUUACUGAACAUCCUAGAAAUAGAUUUUUUUUUUUUUUUUUUUUUGAGACGGAGUCUCGCUCUGUCGCCCAGGCUGGAGUGCAGUGGCGCGAUCUCGGCUCACUGCAAGCUCCGCCUCCCGGGUUCACGCCAUUCUCCUGCCUCAGCCUCCCGAGUAGCUGGGACUACCGGCGCCCGCUACCACGCCCGGCUAAUUUUUUGUAUUUUUAGUAGAGACGGGGUUUCACCGUGUUAGCCAGAAUGGUCUCGAUCUCCUGACCUCGUGAUCCGCCCGCCUCGGCCUCCCAAAGUGCUGGGAUUACAGGCGUGAGCCACCGCGCCCGGCCAGAAAUAGAUUUUAUAGUUAAAGCGAUGUUCUUCAAGCUGGACUUUAUGCCACAAGGGGAGUGUAUUCUAAAGGGGAAGAAAAGGAUUGUGGUUUAAAAGAACAAUUGUAAUAUUUCCUUCAUUCUGAGGUGUAUUUUUCUCACAUUUUCAUAUUGUAAUUAGGAUACCUGUUAACAUUGGUGUACAUUUAAUGUAGUAGUACUUUUUCUCCUUUUGCCCUGCAAGUUGUCACUAAAUUUGUGCUAUCAUAAUUGUUACCUUCAUAGAAUGCUUAAAUAGUGGUACUUCUUUGACUUGUUAGGUUUGGACUAUUUUCCUUUUCUUCUUCCAUUUGUGAGGUAAAUUAGUGGUUAUUUUGGUGCUGGGUGCUAAGAAACUCGCAAAACAAGGGCCCUGCUCAAGAAGGAUUGAAACUUAGUCCUUGCUGGGUACAAAUUUAGAAAUUUGUUAUAUAACUGUGGGGCAAGGGACAACAUUUCACCAGGAAGUAGCAACUCCAUCAUCUUUCAGGAAGGGCUGAUGGUUAGGGCAUCUCUGAAUGAUUAUUGGAGGGAAGUGGCUUUAUGUCACACUUGUUUUCUGUAAGUCUUACUCUGUAUCUACCCGACUUCAGAUCAUGGUGAUUUAAUUACAUGGCCCAAUCAUGUUUUCUUUCCAGGGCUGCUUGAAUGCUUGAAUACUUUUUUUUUUGAGAUGGAGUCUCGUUCUGUCGCCCAGGCUGGAGUGCAGUGGUGCAAUCUCGGCUCAUUGCAAGCUCCGCCUCCCGGGUUCACACCAUUCUCCUGCCUCAGCCUCCCGAGUAGCCAGGACUACAGGCAUGUGCCACCAUGCCUGGCUAAUGUUUUGUAUUUUUAGUAGAGAUAGGGUUUCACCAUGUUAGCCAGGAUGGUCUCGAUCUCCUGACCUCGUGAUCCGCCCGCCUUGGCCUCCCAAAGUGCUAGGAUUACAGGCGUGAGCCACCGCGCCUGGCCAGAAUGAAUACUUUUAAUUACUACUAUGAGUCUUUUUUCAAAGUGCCUCCACCUUAAAAAAAAUUCCUUAUUUUAUUCACUUGCCAGAAUAAUGUUGCAUUUGAACCAUGCCAACGGUAGCUUAUUAAAACAGCAUUUAUUUUUCUCAUUCAUGGGUCAGCUGAACUUGUCUCUAGCCUUCAGAUUGGGCUCAGGUGGGCUUUGUGUUUGUCAUUCUGGAGCCUAGUUCCAGAGAGCAGUGGCUGCUUGAGUGUGGACUUGCUUAUGGUGGGCCAAAGAGGGGCAAGGGAAAGCGCAUUUACACUUUCUCGUAUUCCAUUGCCCAGAGAUGGCAUAUAGCCGAUCCCAAGUCAGUGCUAUUCAUUCAUUUUUUUAAAAAAAUUUAUUUAUUUAUUUAUUUAUUUAUUUUCAGACGGGGUCUUGCACUGUUGCCCGGGCUGGAGUGCAGUGGUGGCAUCUCCGCUCACUGCAACCUCCACCUCCCAGGUUCACAUGAUUCUCCUGCCUCAGCCUCCUGAGUAGCUGGGAUUACAGGUGUCUGCCACUGCGCCCGGCUAAUUUUUUGUAUUUUUAAGGGAGACUGGGUGUCACUAUGUUGGCCAGACAGAUCUCAAACUCCUGACCUCCUGAUCCGCCCUCCUCAGCCUCCCAAAGUGCUGGGAUUAUAGGCAUGAGUCACUGCGCCCGGCCUAUUCAUUCAUUCUUACAGUGAAUUAGUAAAUUCAACAAAUAGGUUUUUUUAAAGCAAUUAAGGCACUGAGGAUAUACAGAGAGUAAAAUAGAUGUCUCCUGACUUCUACUUGGAAUUUUCUUUCCCUUACAGUUUUGAUAGCUGCUUUCUCUUGAAUAACUAUGUCAUCUCUUUCCACUUUGCAUUGCUCCCAAGAGAGUAAUGUAAAAGUUUUAUCUGUGCAUGCAUAUUCAUGACACAUUCAUUUGUCAUUAUUUAUCAAAAACCUGUUCCCUUCCCUGGCACUGGAGACAUUGGAGAAUGACAGUCUCAAGCAGUGCAGAGAUGUAAGCAGGCAGAGGUAAGGACUUUGGUCUCAAUAGCCUACAGGGUGCUUCAUCCACUCACUGUAUUCUGUGUGCCUGUGCCGCGGUGCAGGUGGUCAGUUGGAACCCCUGAUGGGUAUCUGGGCCACUGCCCAGGCCACACAGAGCCUUUGUGCAAAUUAGAAAAGGCCCUUCCAAAGAUACUUUAUGAACGACUUGUAAUAAUUUAGUGAUUUUAUUUUCCAAAGCAAGGCAUUUGGUUGCUACCUGCUAGAACUGUUACAGUAAAUACACAGAUCUAUUUUGUGAGCAAAUAGUACUGCCUUGGAUGUGGUACCCUUGUGCAGUGCACAACUUGGACAGUUCAUACACAAUGUUGUAUUGAGAUGAUUGUUAUUCUACAUUGUAUUUAUUUAGAUAGUGGGAUUGAAAAUAGGCUAAGAUGGAGAACUGGGUGGGGAACAAUUUGUAAUCCUUUUUAGUUCAUAUGUCACAAUCACAGAAUUGAGACUAGCUAGUUUAAAUCCCUGCAUCUUGCACAUGGUGAGGAAAGGUGAGGACAUUUAGAUGACCUUUGCCUGUCACCACACAGCUGUAUGGUAGCAGAGCUGGGCGUGAAACCUGCAUUCCUGGCCUCUCCUUUUGUGGUGCUUACAGUGCUGUGUUAGGUCCAGUUUUACCUCUUAAAUCUGUAUUAUUACUUUUUUUUCGAGACCAGAUCUUACUCUGUCGCCCAGGCUGGAGUGCAGUGGCGUGAUCUCGGCUUGCUGCAAUCUCUGCAAUUCUCAUGCCUCAGCCUCCCAAGUAGCUGGGACUACAGGCGUGAGCCACCGUGCCUGGCUAAUUUUUGUAUUUUUAGUAGAGAUGGGGUUUCACCAUGUUGGCCAGGCUGGUCUUGAACUCCUGACCUCAGGUGAUCCGCCCGUUGCGGCCUCCCUAAGUGCUGGGAUUAUAGGCGUGAGCCACUGCGCCCGGCCUGAAAUGUGUAUUCUUAAGUCCGCCUUUCAAAGUUGAGUACUGCAUUCUUGCGGCUCUACCUAAGUUUCUCCUAGAAUCUCCCUGCACUUCUUGUUUUGCUGCCAUCAGGUAAUUUGUGCAUUAGAACUAGCUUGGAACAGAAUGGGUAAACUUCUGUGAAGUUAGACACUUGCCUCUUAGAGGCAUAUCCAGUGAGUCUUUAAAGCCCUACGUUAUAGAAAAAUGUGAAGUAUGUCUAAUAAAGGAGUACAGUGGAAGGUUUAAAAGCACAUUGCUGAUUAGUGGGGUCAGGAUGGGAGGAGAGCCCUGAUUUUAAUGCAGUGUCAUAGUCUCAUAGGUGAUUUCCCCAAAAGCAAAUAAAUGCUCGAUGGAUUUUGGGUCCACCAUGCAUCUCUGAAGUAGAAGUGACAGAUUUUCAAGGCUAAGGUAAGUAUAGCAUUUUCUCAACCCUAUUACAAUAGAGCACAGGAUCAUAACUGUUCUGUUUGCUCUGAUGCGUCCCGCAGAGCAGUGCUUUUUCUCGGUGUGAACUGUGGAUCACUUGUCUCAGUCAUCAGGAUUCCUGGACCCUGUAGGAUUUACUCUCAAUCUUUAGGGGUAGAGACUAGGAGCCUACAUUUUGAACAAGCAUCUUUUUAUUUUGAUGAAGUUUGCAUUAUUACUCCUAACAACGUGCCCUUUGGCAGGUAGCUUCCACUUUUCUGGCCUCAUUAUCUGUAAAAUUGCAUACUUAGUUAUCAUUGAGGUCUCAAAUGCAGUUCGGGUUCCUGGUUGGUGAACAAUUAGAUGGGAAGGCUGAAAAAAAAAAUACUCCUGAGAUUCUGAAUCUGUAAGUAUGCAAUGGGACCUGAGAAUCAAUCUAAUUUCUAAAAGAUUCCCAGAUAGAACUUUGUUGAGCUAUGUUUAGGGACCAGUGCACACCUUGGUGAUAGAACCUUUUUGAAACUUUGAAAAAGUUAAAAGGGUUCUGUGUAAUGUUACCUAAGAAGCUUAUUUUUAAAAAAGGAAAGCAGUGCUUAGGGCCAUAUUGUUUUGAAAUAGGAUCUGAGCACCAUUUAAAUUUUUAUAAAUUAUUUUUUAGAGGCAUCACUUCUUUAAAGCCCAUCAGAUUAAUGUGCCAUUGGUUUGAAAACCAUGACAUGAGAUGAUUUCUUAAGGUUUUAUUUGUGUCAGACAUGAAUUUUAGAGUAUUUCUGGGCUAUAGGUCAUUACAGCUUUACUUAUUUAUUUUUUGGAGACAGGGUCUCACUCUGUCACCCAGGCUGGAGUGCAGUGUCGUGGUCUUGGGUCACUGCAUCCUUGACCUCCCCAGCUCAAGCGAUCCUCCCGCCUCAGCCUCCCGAGUAGAAGGUACUACAGGUGUGUGACACCACGCCUGGCUCAUUUUUGCAUUUUGUGUAGAGAGGGGGUUUUGCCAUUUUACCCAGGCUGGUCUCGAACUCCUGAGCUGAUCCUCCCACCUCGGCCUCCCAACGUGCUGGGAUUACAGGCAUUAGCCACUGUGCCCAGCUGGGUAUGGAUUUCUGAGUGGAGGGAAUGUGAACAAAGGAGGGCCCAGGCAUGUUUGCAGAGUGGCUGGGGGCCCUGCUUCACCACGGCAUAGGGACGGGUGCAGUAGGAAGAAAGGUAGCCUCAAGGCCCCCAUAAAUAAAUUGGUGCAUUAAGGAAGGAAUAUUAAUCACAUCCAGGAGGGCUCUGCCCUAACUGCUGAGAAUCAUAAAAGAAAUGGGGACAUAUUCUGGCGAAAUAACAGCUUUGUUAAUUGAGCUCUUACUGUGUGCCUUUGCACUGUGUUAAGCACAUGGUGUUAUCACACUUGCUACUCACAACAGCUCUGAGGUUGAUAGUACAGGUAUCUUCUUUUUAUGGAGCAGGACUCUGAGACAUCAUAAUUGCUUGGUAUAUGCAGCCAGAGUUGGAAAUCCUAUCUGUCUGAUUUUGGAAACUGUGUGCUUACCAUUACAUAUCUUAUGUGGAAAUAAAAUGUAUAUGAUUAAUUACAAAGCUGAAAAUCGUAGUUGAAGCAUCAUAUAGUGCACAGGGCAAGCAAAGCAGCAUAAAAGGCUUCAUCUGUAAGGGUAGGUUUGUUGGGUAGGAGCUUUUUGGGGGAGGUGACUUUAGGAUCAGUUGUAGCAUGAGAGAAUAUGACACCUUCUUCCUUUAGAGGAUCUAAAGGUGUAGCUUUAGAGGAUUGUAGGGUGCCUUUGCCCAUUGUGUCAUUUGGUCCUUCUUAAAAUUUGAGUGUUUAUUCUCUACAUGGCACUCUUUUAAGCCUUUGUGUGAAUUAACUCAGUCUUCUCAGCAAUCCCCCAUUUUUUCAUAUGUGGAAACUGAGGCAUGUUAUGAUACAAAGCUUGUCCAAGAAUUCAGAGCUAGCUUGUCCAAGAAUUCAGAGCUAGUAAGUGAGGGAACUGGGAUUUGAAUUUAAGCAGUCUGUCUCUAGAGUCUGCUCAGCUGGCCUUUUUUUCUUUCUUCUUCUUCUUCUUCUUUUUUUUUUUUUUUGUAUAAUAGGCCUGUGAGUUGGGAAGAGCAGGGUUUGUUUGGUGAGAAAGUUGCACCUUAGUGAAUACCCAAGGUCUGAGGGAGGCUUGGAGCCAGCUCUGCAACCUGGCUCCCUUCUUUCAUUAGCUUGACCCAAGCACAGGGAGAUGACUGGGGCUCUGCCUUCAUCUUCUCUGCAAACGGUCAGGGAUACUCAUGCAGUUUUUGAGUUUAAGUAGUAAACUCCUAAACUUCAAGUCAUGUUUGUAUUAGUGAUUUCACUUGACCUCAGUACAACUCUGUAAAAGAGGCAGGGAUGGAUGAUGUCAUUUGUCAAAUGGUAAAACUGAGGCGAAACAACUUGGCAUUGUUGGUGUUGUGCGAAGUACAUGCAUAGGCUUUGGAUUUGAGUUUGGCUCUGCCACUAACUUGAUCUAUGUCUUCAGGCAAGUAACUUAAAUGCUCUGAGUGUUGCAUUCUCUGUGAAGUGGAAAUAGCUGUACUUUGCCCAAGAGUUGUGAGAGUGACAUGAAUUGCUAUAUGUGAGGUUCUUAGCAUAGUGCCUGGCAAGUAGAAGGUACUCAUCUGUGAAUGGGGUAGAUAGCAGCUGUCUUCAUCACUGUCAUCAUUGUUGGCUCACAUCAAAUCAGGACCAGAAAACCCUGUUGACUUCUGGGUCUUAAACUGCUGUAUCAGUGAGGGGCUUCCUCCUCAUACUCAUUGCCAGGAGUAGAGUAAGGCUUUUAAUUUCAUCUCUAACCAACUCUGAUAGGGCUGGAAAUGUGUAUGGAGUUCCAGACCCACCAUGGGGCCCCAGUGCUAGCUUCUUAGCCCUCCUUUGUAAGGUUUGCACUAGUUUGAUGGGAGAGGGAUUUUUUUUGUCUUGAUUCUGAAGCUCUUAAAGAAAUGCUCCUUUUUCUCCAUAACUUGAGGAUUUCACAAUUGUAUUGGAAUUAUUGGUGUUAAGGAGUUAGGUCCAUCUCUUGGCAGCUUGUGAAGGGUGGGCAGGCACCUGUGAAUUCUUCACUGGCUUCUUGUAAGAAUGACUUUACUGGAGGGUGCUGAGUUUGUGAUUAUCUCCUCUGCUGCUAGAAAACUCCGUGAACCCUGGUACAUAUAGCGUGAUAAAUCAAGUCCUGUUUUUGCUCCUAACUUGCAUUAUGGUGUUUGAUACUAUAUCUUCAUUUCUCCCAUGGUAGUAAUAACACUGUUGGAAAGAGCUCUCAGUUGGAAGUUGAAGAUCCAGGUUCUAGUUGAGGCACCAGAGUUUCCUUGGGCAAGUUGCCAUACCUUUUUGGGCCUUGGUUUCCUCAUCUCAAUAAAAUGAGUUUCUGUUC